AGAGGGAGGCCCCGCGCAGAGUGGGAACCAUCGCCCGGUGCGGGCCUGAACUUCCAGGGCCGGCUACUCCUCGGCAGAGCGACCGCGCGGUGUCUCAGAGCGCGGCCCGGAGCCGCACUAAGAGCGCUGGACGGCGGGAGAGAGGCUCGGAGGACCGGUAGCUCCCAGCAAAGCGGCCCAGCGGAUGUCGGGAGCUAUCUUCGGGCCCCUGGAGGGCCCGAGCUCCCUGGAUGCCCCGAGCAUCCACCCGCUGGUGUGCCCGCUGUGCCACGUGCAGUACGAGCGCCCGUGUCUUCUGGACUGUUUCCACGACUUCUGUGCCGGCUGCCUGCGUGGCCGCGCGACCGACGGCCGCCUCACCUGCCCGCUGUGCCAACACCAGACGGUGCUGAAGGGUCCCAGCGGGCUCCCGCCGGUGGACCGGCUGCUGCAGUUCCUGGUGGACAGCUCAGGGGAUGGCGUGGAGGCGGUGCGCUGUGCCAACUGUGACCUGGAGUGCAGCGAGCAGGACGUGGAGACCACGUACUUCUGCAACACGUGCGGACAGCCCCUAUGCGCGCGCUGCCGCGACGAGACGCACCGAGCACGCAUGUUCGCGCGCCACGACAUCGUGGCCCUGGGUCAGCGAAGCCGCGACGUGCCCCAGAAGUGCACGCUGCACGCAGAGCCCUACCUCUUGUUCUCCACCGACAAGAAGUUGCUGUUGUGCAUCCGCUGCUUCCGCGACAUGCAGAAGGAGAGCCGGGCACACUGCGUGGACCUGGAAUCGGCUUACGUGCAGGGCUGCGAGCGGCUGGAGCAGGCGGUGCUGGCCGUGAAGGCCCUGCAGACGGCCACGCGGGAGGCCAUCGCGCUGCUGCAGGCCAUGGUGGAGGAGGUGCGGCACAGCGCCGCCGAGGAGGAGGACGCUAUCCACGCCCUCUUCGGCAGCAUGCAGGACAGGCUGGCAGAGAGGAAAGCGCUGCUGCUGCAGGCUGUGCAGAGCCAAUACGAAGAGAAGGACAAGGCCUUCAAGGAGCAGCUCUCUCACUUGGCCACCUUGCUGCCCACCCUGCAGGUCCACCUGGUCAUCUGCUCCUCCUUCCUCAGCUUGGCCAACAAGGCUGAGUUCCUGGACCUGGGCUAUGAGCUGAUGGAGAGGCUGCAGGGCAUCGUCACGCGGCCGCACCACCUAAGGCCUAUUCAGAGCAGCAAGAUUGCCAGUGACCACCGAGCUGAAUUCGCGCGCUGUCUGGAGCCACUGCUGCUGCUGGGGCCACGUCGGGUGGCAGCUGCUGCAAGUGGUGCUAACACGCUGGCAGGGGGCUUAGGCCCCAAGGCGCUGACGGGGCCCCACUGCCCCUCCCCAGUAGGAAAGAUGUCGGGGUCACCCGUCCAAAAGCCCACGCUGCACCGGUCCAUCAGCACCAAGGUGCUGCUGGCGGAGGGCGAGAACACGCCCUUCGCAGAGCACUGCCGCCACUAUGAGGACUCCUACCGGCACCUGCAGGCAGAGAUGCAGAGCCUAAAGGACCAGGUACAGGAGCUGCACCGAGACCUCACCAAGCACCACUCGCUCAUCAAGGCGGAGAUCAUGGGAGACGUCCUGCACAAGUCCCUGCAACUGGACGUGCAGAUCGCCUCGGAGCACGCCUCCUUAGAGGGCAUGAGGGUCGUCUUCCAGGAGAUUUGGGAGGAAGCCUAUCAGCGAGUGGCUAAUGAGCAGGAGAUUUAUGAAGCCCAGCUCCAUGACCUUCUCCAGCUGAGGCAGGAGAAUGCCUACCUGACCACCAUCACCAAGCAGAUCACGCCCUACGUCCGCUCCAUUGCCAAGGUGAAGGAGCGGCUGGAGCCCAGGUUUCAGGCACCCGUGGAUGAGCAGUCAGAGAGUCUACAGAACACGCACGACGACAGCAGGAACAACGCGGCCUCAGCCAGGAAUAAUCCAGGAAGUGUCCCGGAAAAGAGAGAGAAGACAUCAGAGCCUAAAGGAAACAGCUGGGCUCCGAACGGCCUCUCAGAAGAGCCUCUACUGAAAAAUAUGGAUCAUCACAGAUCCAAACAGAAAAAUGGGGGCGAUGUCCCCACAUGGAGGGAACACCCGACUUAGCAAAUGGGACCGGUCCCCAGGGUCAGGCUCUUAGAGCAGGCACAAGACUGGGACACUGGACAGAAGGUUGUUCCCAUGAUGGUUUUUUUUAUUUUUUAUUUUUGAGAUGGAGUUUCGCUCUGUUGCCCAGGCUGGAGUGUAAUGGUGCAAUCUCGGCUCACUGCAACCUCUGCCUCCUGGGUUCAAGCGAUUCUCCUGCCUCAGCCUCCCGAGUAGCUGGGAUUACAGGCGCCUGACACCACGCCCCGCUAAUUUUUUGUAUUUUUAGUAGAGAUGGGGUUUCACCAUGUUGGCCAGGCUGGUCUCAAACGCCAGACCUCAGGUGAUCCACCUGCCUCAGCCUCCCAAAGUGCUGAGAUUACAGGGGUGAGUCACCGCGCCUGGCCAAUGUUGUUGUUGUUUUUAAGACAGAAUUUCACUCUUUGUUGCCCAGGCUGGAGUGCAAUGGCGCAAUCUCUGGCUCACCGCAACCUCCGCCUCCCAGGUUCAAGCGAUUCUCCUACCUCAGCCCCCAGAGUAGCUGGGAUUACAGGCAUGUACCAUCACACCCGGCUAAUUUUUUGUAUUUUAAGUAGAGAGGGGGUUUCUCCAUGUUGGUCAGGCUGGCCUCGAACUCCCAACCUCAGGUGAUCCGCCCACCUCGGCCUCCCAAAAUGCUGGGAUUACAGGGGUAAGCCACUGUGCCCGGCCGGUUAUUUCUUUAAAAGGUAAUCAUUUGUCAAGAGUAAAACCCAGAAGCUCUGACAGGCCAUAAUUUCAGAUCCUUUGGCUUGGGCAGUUUUGAUUUUCCCCGUGUUUGCAUGGCAUGAAGUCUUCGUCCUUGUCACAGUAGCUUGGGAUGACUCCCAGUCCACAUGGAAAACAUCAGGGAGUGACAAUCCAGCAAGAAAUCCCUCGCUAGUUCCACACCUACGCACCGAGCGUCGGUGUGCCAGGCCCUGUGCUGGGCAGAGUGUGGUAUGUCAGGGUGUGCCGGUUUUAGGUAACAAGACUCCACCACUGAGUGGCACCUGCCCUAUUGCAAAGGAAUCCAGUUCCUCCGGAAUAACAGUCCCACUGUUAACCUGGUGCUACUGGGAAGUUCCACACAGUAAUCUGAGCAGUGACUCAUGGAAGGAUGAGGAACGUUUGCUCCAGCUUCUCUCCCUUUCCAGCAAGGGCAGAGCUCCUAAAGCCAGGGGUUAGCACCUGGCCAGCUUAUGUGGCAGAUGGUCUCAGUUACAACUUCGCUGCUUUCCCAAACUCCUGCAGCCCUCCUGAGUCCGACUUCCGUUGAUAGCAAGGCACUGGGUGGCAGCAACCUUUUUUCUAGUAGUUUUUUCCCAGCAGUUUUCCAUUUCUCCACAGUAUCCUUUUCAUUUAGAGGAGCUUAAUAAAUGCUUUUUAAAAAGUAACCCACGUGACGUAAAAUUUUACAAGUUUUUGUGGCAAAAUGAUGCCCAGAUAGUCACAUUUAAGCAAAUAUUCAGCUUGAUUCAGUGAUUAACAGCAAAUGGGUCUACGUGCUAACAUGGCAGCACAUUCAACACAUAACACAUCACUCACAUUGACGUCCACUGUCCCUGCACCUGCUACUUCAGGGGCACUGAGGCUCCUGUUCCAAGGCCUUACAAACCUAUGUGGUGGCCUGCAGGGCAAAAGGAAUUAUCAUUACAACUGGUUAGAGGUAGGAAUUCAGAAAGAAAUUGAGGAGGCCAAACACACGUCGUUUGAGGCUAAAGGCUUAAGACGCUUCUUACCCAAGAGUGACCUCAGAGUUUCACAUCCCAGACAAUCACACUGUGGUUGAGUGAAAUCAAGUGCAGUUUUAUUUAAGAACUGGAAAGAAUAAUCAGUAUCUGUGAAAGAAAAUCCAAUUUAGAAUAUUUAAAUAAACAUUUAUGUAAAAAGAA